AUCUGUCCUGCCGCCUUCGCCCACGCCCUGCACUCCGGGACCGUCCCUGCGCGCUCUGGGCGCACCAUGGCCCGCGGGGCUGCGCUGGCGCUGCUGCUCUUCGGCCUGCUGGGUGUUCUGGUCGCCGCCCCGGAUGGUGGUUUCGAUUUAUCCGAUGCCCUUCCUGACAAUGAAAACAAGAAACCCACUGCAAUCCCCAAGAAACCCAGUGCUGGGGAUGACUUUGACUUAGGAGAUGCUGUUGUUGAUGGAGAAAAUGACGACCCACGACCACCGAACCCACCCAAACCGAUGCCAAAUCCAAACCCCAACCACCCUAGUUCCUCCGGUAGCUUUUCAGAUGCUGACCUUGCGGAUGGCGUUUCAGGUGGAGAAGGAAAAGGAGGCAGUGAUGGUGGAGGCAGCCACAGGAAAGAAGGGGAAGAGGCCGACGCCCCAGGCGUGAUCCCCGGGAUUGUGGGGGCUGUCGUGGUCGCCGUGGCUGGAGCCAUCUCUAGCUUCAUUGCUUACCAGAAAAAGAAGCUAUGCUUCAAAGAAAAUGAUGGCUGAAGACCUAGGGGUGAGCAGAGAACCCAGCCCAGGCCUGCGGAGCGUCCUGACCGUAAUCGUUUUAUCUGCUAAGACAUAGCCUUAAAGCAAACCCUUCCAUCUGCCGCUCCCCUCGCCCUGCUGGCAAAUUCCCACCACGAUGGGAUUCUCAAUCACAUGGCGGAUUCUCUGCCUUCAGUUCCAUAUGCUUUUGCCUUUCUGGAUGCACAGAAGCUCAUUAUAGCAAAUCAUAUUUCUGCAUAAGAGCUUCAGAAAAUGAAGAGAAAUGCAGAUAUUUUCUUUUAAACAUGAAUCUAACAGAAACAGGGCAGUGACUUCCAUGUUUUAAUGAGUUUUGUCCCUAAGUCCAUCCCUGCCAAGGGAACAAACUGGGGCCCAGGGUGGCCACCCUCUUCCCUGCAGUGUCCUAGGUUAAGCUCACUCACGUCCUAAGGAUUUGACCUUCCAGGUCAUGCAUGGAUUUUUAAAUCUUCAACGUUUUUGGCCGUUGACUUGCAUUUCUCACUGCACUUCCUAUGAAGCAGUUCUUAACUCUUUCUGUGAUCAGUGUUCCAAACAGGUACACACCUUGGUUCCUAGAAAAACAAAAUUCAUACGUUGAGGAAUCACCUAAACAUCUCCUGAUCUUCACACUGUAAGGCGUGUUGGGAAUUGGUGGGUGGUCAGGUCCCUAUUCACACAUUUGAGCACGGAGCCUCUGCGGCCGUCUUCCUUGGAUUCUCUCAUAUCCCUGAAAAACACAAAUUGUACCUGGAUUUUCCUUCUGUUUCCAAAGUCCACCAACUUGUUCUUCAAUGUAAUUGAUUUUAACUUGUUUUCUUUCUUUUACUUUUCUUAUUUUUUUCUUUCUUUUCAUUUUUUUCUUAUUUCUUUUCCUUCUAUUUAUUUUACUUUUCUUAUUUGUUAUAUGUUAUUUCUUUUUCUUUUCUUACUUUUCUUCUUUUUUCAUUUUUCUUUUUUAAAUUGGAGUCUCACUCUGUUGCCCAGGCUGGAGUGCAGUGGUGCAAUCUUGGCUCACUGCAGCCUCCACCUCCUGGGUUCAAGCGAUUCUCCUGCCUCAGCCUCCCGAGUAGCUGGGACUACAGGCACACACCACCACACCCAGCUAAUUUUUGUAUUUUUAGUAGAGACGGGGUUUCUCCAUGUUGGCCAGGCUGAUCUCGAACUUCUGACUUCAGGUGAUCUGCCUGCCUCAACCUUCCAAAGUGCUGGGAUUACAGGUGUGAGCCACUGUGCCUGGCCCUUUUUCUUUUUUCUUUUUUUUUUUCUCUUAUUUCUUUUUUCUUAUUUGUUUUCCUUUUUGCUUUUUCUUUUUAUCUUAUUUCUUUUACUUAUUUUUCUUUUUUUUACUUUUAUUUCUUCUCCGUUUUUCCUCAUUCUUUUCCUCUUAUUUCUUUGACUUUUCUGAUUUCUUUUUUUUUCUUAUUUUCCUUUUUUUUUCAUAUUCCUUUUAAUUUUUUCUUACUUCUUUUACUUUUCUUAUUUGCCCUCUUGUGGAAAUGAGGCACAGCCUCCCUUAUGGUUGAGCCGUAGUUCUAGCUGAGCACGGAUGGUUUGAUCCUCCUGUGUUGGGGCACUGUAUGGUGUGAGGGCACAAAACCUUGACCCACAUGGGUCUGGUCACCUUCUCACAGAGGUCACCUUUACAGCCCCCCAACUCUUUGAAGGAUGUGUCCCAAGGUGUCUCAAGUCUGAUGCAAUGAAAGCUGCCCCCCAUUGACCACAGGACUGAGUCCAGAAUGUCCUGCGUGUUUCCCAGAGUGUCUGUCCUAACACCGCUUAAAGAUUAGCCACUGCUAGACAGUGAUCCUCAGGUAUAUGGUCUCAGGAUUGGCCCCAAGCACACGGUGUGUGUGUGUGUAUAAAUAUAUCUUCACAAAGCAUAGGUACCCAUUAAAGCCAUAUUGCUUUGCUGAAUGGUUCUAAUAGCUACAGAUGAUUUCUAGCCUGAAAGAAAAGCACCACGAAUUGUUUGAAGUUGACUUGUCAGAUGUGGCAUGCUUGGUCUAAGUUUUGACAGGAAGGGUAUGUGGGUAGGGGUGUACGGAGCAUCUCAUGAGACCAGUUCUCCUCCUGAGAGGUCCGUGAUGUUGGAACUGUUGCCCCAGAUGGACUUUGCCCUUGUGAGACUUUAUACUUUUCAAUGCAGUUUUUCCCUCUUUAAAACUCGCCAGCUUUUAUGUAGUGUUUUAUAAAAUUACAGGAAUAAAAAGAAUAUCUUUUAUGCUUUUUAACCAAUGAGGGGAGAGGGAGAAAUUAUUUGUCCUCUGAAAUGAAUGCAGGUUUUCAAUUUCUAGCCAGGACAGUUUGCUGCAAAAUGCACCCGUGUUGACAACUUGUGACUGGCAGAACAAAUGACAUUUGUGGUGAACAUUUUCGGAUCAUUUCGAAUGUUCUUCUCUUCAGGGGGUUUUCCUCUCUUUUUCUUAAAUCAAAGAAUUUGGCCCUUUAUGUGGGAGUCAUUUAGUGGUUAGGGAGAACAGUUGAAACUGUGGAGUUCACGUAGCGUAAACUGGCGAGGCUGUCUCUGCUGCUGUCAUUAAAAGUUACGCUGCUGGCUUGGCACGGUGGUUCACACCUGUAAUCCCAGCAUUUUGGGAGGCCGAGGUGGGCAGAUCACGAAGUCAGGAGAUCGAGACCAUCCUGGCUAACAUGGUGAAACCCCGUCUCUACUAAAAAUACAAAAAAUUAGCUGGGCAUGGUGGCGGGCGCCUGUAGUCCCAGCUACUCGGGAGGCUGAGGCAAGAGAAUGGCGUGAACCCUGGAGGCGGAGGUUGCAGUGAGCCGAGAUCGCGCCACUGCGUUCCAGCCUGGGCGACAGAGCAAGACUCUGUCUCAAAAAAAAAAAAAAAAGAAAAGAAAAAGAAAAGUUACGCUGCUGCACCAUACAAACGUGUUCCUUUAUGAAGGCAUUUGAACCACAGAUGGGGCCGUUUUACAAAUAGCACGGUCUUUGUGAGGGGGAAACGCAUGGCCACAGAUUCGAUGAGCUUCUGCUGCUUCCCUUUGUGUUGAAAACGUGGGUGUUCCUUCACACCAACACUGGAAAUAAAUAAAUACCUAUUGAUCUGUG